AGUGCGGCUGCGCGGGCGUCUCAGGCUCUGAGGCCCGGGCGCCGCGGCUCUUUUGUUUCUCCGUUGGGGCCGAGCCCGGGCCCUAGUUGGAGCCGGAGUCGGAGUCGGAGUCGGAUCCGGAUUCGGAUUAGCAGCCCGGGAAGAGUGCCGUGGCACAGGCGCCGGAGGGAGCGCGACCCUCGGACCCCGCCUGGCCCGCGGGGCUGGGACCCGGCCCCGGCCUGCCCGAUGGGGCGCGCGGCCCCGGAGAUGCGCCCUCGCCCGGCCCCGCGCCCCCGGCCCCGCGCCCCCGGCCCGCCCGCCCCGGCCCGCGCCUCCGCCUGAGUCCCCCGCGCCUUGGCCCGCCACCCCCCGCCCCGCGCCCCCGGCCCGCCUGCGCCAUGGAGCCCGGCCGCGGCGGCACAGAGACCGUGGGCAAGUUCGAGUUCUCCCGCAAGGACCUGAUCGGCCACGGCGCCUUCGCGGUGGUCUUCAAGGGCCGCCACCGCGAGAAGCACGAUUUGGAGGUCGCCGUCAAGUGCAUUAACAAGAAGAACCUCGCCAAGUCUCAGACGCUGCUGGGGAAGGAAAUCAAAAUCCUGAAGGAACUGAAACAUGAAAACAUCGUGGCCCUGUACGACUUCCAGGAAAUGGCUAAUUCUGUCUACCUGGUUAUGGAGUACUGCAACGGUGGGGACCUGGCCGACUACCUGCACGCCAUGCGCACGCUGAGCGAGGACACCAUCAGGCUCUUCCUGCAGCAGAUCGCGGGCGCCAUGCGGCUUCUGCACAGCAAAGGCAUCAUCCACCGCGACCUGAAACCGCAGAACAUCCUGCUGUCCAACCCCGCCGGCCGCCGCGCCAACCCCAACAGCAUCCGCGUCAAGAUCGCUGACUUCGGCUUCGCGCGGUACCUCCAGAGCAACAUGAUGGCGGCCACACUCUGCGGCUCCCCCAUGUACAUGGCCCCCGAGGUCAUCAUGUCCCAGCACUACGACGGGAAGGCGGACCUGUGGAGCAUCGGCACCAUCGUCUACCAGUGCCUGACGGGGAAGGCGCCCUUCCAGGCCAGCAGCCCCCAGGACCUGCGCCUGUUCUACGAGAAGAACAAGACGUUGGUCCCCACCAUCCCCCGGGAGACCUCGGCCCCGCUGCGGCAGCUGCUCCUGGCCCUACUGCAACGCAACCACAAGGACCGCAUGGACUUCGAUGAGUUUUUUCAUCACCCUUUCCUCGAUGCCAGCCCCUCGGUCAGGAAAUCCCCACCCGUGCCUGUGCCCUCGUACCCAAGCUCGGGGUCCGGCAGCAGCUCCAGCAGCAGCUCCACCUCCCACCUGGCCUCCCCGCCGUCCCUGGGCGAGAUGCAGCAGCUGCAGAAGACCCUGGCCUCCCCGGCUGACACCGCUGGCUUCCUGCACAGCUCCCGGGACUCUGGUGGCAGCAAGGACUCUUCCUGUGACACAGACGACUUCGUCAUGGUCCCCGCGCAGUUUCCAGGUGACCUGGUGGCUGAGGCGCCCAGUGCCAAACCCCCGCCAGACAGCCUGAUGUGCAGUGGGAGCUCACUGGUGGCCUCUGCGGGCUUGGAGAGCCACGGCCGGACCCCAUCUCCAUCCCCACCCUGCAGCAGCUCCCCCAGUCCCUCAGGCCGGGCUGGCCCGUUCUCCAGCAGCAGGUGCGGCGCCUCUGUCCCCAUCCCAGUCCCCACGCAGGUGCAGAACUACCAGCGCAUUGAGCGAAACCUGCAGUCACCCACCCAGUUCCAAACACCUCGGUCCUCUGCCGUCCACAGGUCAGGCAGGGCUGCUGAGGCCUCCCCUCCUAAUAUCUGCCUUGUCUUCAGGUCCUCUGCCAUCCGCAGGUCAGGCAGCACCAGCCCCCUGGGCUUUGCAAGGGCCAGCCCCUCGCCCCCUGCCCACGCUGAGCAUGGAGGCGUCCUGGCCAGGAAGAUGUCUCUGGGUGGAGGCCGGCCCUACACGCCAUCUCCUCAAGUUGGAACCAUCCCUGAGCGGCCAGGCUGGAGCGGGACGCCCUCCCCACAGGGAGCUGAGAUGCGGGGUGGCAGGUCCCCUCGUCCAGGCUCCUCUGCACCCGAGCACUCUCCCCGCACUUCCGGGCUGGGCUGCCGCCUGCACAGCGCCCCCAACCUGUCUGACUUGCACGUCGUCCGCCCCAAGCUGCCCAAACCCCCCACGGACCCCCUGGGAGCUGUGUUCAGCCCACCACAGGCCAGCCCUCCCCAGCCGUCCCACGGCCUGCAGUCCUGCCGGAACCUGCGGGGCUCACCCAAGCUGCCCGACUUCCUGCAGCGAAACCCCCUGCCCCCCAUCCUGGGCUCCCCCACCAAGGCUGUGCCCUCCUUUGACUUCCCGAAGACCCCCAGCUCCCAGAACCUGCUGGCCCUCCUAGCCCGGCAGGGCGUGGUGAUGACGCCCCCUCGAAACCGGACGCUGCCCGACCUCUCGGAGGUGGGACCCUUCCAUGGUCAGCCGUUGGGCCCUGGCCUGCGGCCAGGCGAGGACCCCAAGGGCCCCUUUGGCCGGUCUUUCAGCACCAGCCGCCUCACUGACCUGCUCCUUAAGGCGGCGUUUGGGACACAAGCCCCGGACCCGGGCAGCACGGAGAGCCUGCAGGAGAAGCCCAUGGAGAUCGCACCCUCAGCUGGCUUUGGAGGGAGCCUGCACCCAGGAGCCCGUGCUGGGGGCACCAGCAGCCCUUCCCCGGUGGUCUUCACCGUGGGCUCUCCCCCGAGCGGGAGCACGCCCCCCCAGGGCCCCCGCACCAGGAUGUUCUCAGCGGGCCCCACUGGCUCUGCCAGCUCUUCUGCCCGCCACCUGGUGCCUGGGCCCUGCAGCGAGGCCCCAGCCCCUGAGCUCCCUGCUCCAGGACACGGCUGCAGCUUUGCCGACCCCAUUACUGCGAACCUGGAGGGGGCUGUGACCUUCGAGGCCCCCGACCUCCCUGAGGAGACCCUCAUGGAGCAAGAGCACACGGAGAUCCUGCGUGGCCUGCGCUUCACGCUGCUGUUCGUGCAGCACGUCCUGGAGAUCGCAGCCCUGAAGGGCAGCGCCAGUGAGGCGGCGGGGGGCCCUGAGUACCAGCUGCAGGAGAGUGUGGUGGCCGACCAGAUCAGCCUGCUGAGCCGAGAAUGGGGCUUCGCGGAACAGCUGGUGCUGUACCUGAAGGUGGCCGAGCUACUGUCCUCCGGCCUGCAAAGUGCCAUCGACCAGAUCCGGGCCGGCAAGCUCUGCCUGUCGUCCACUGUGAAGCAGGUGGUGCGCAGGCUGAAUGAGCUGUACAAGGCCAGCGUGGUGUCCUGCCAGGGCCUGAGCCUGCGGCUGCAGCGCUUCUUCCUGGACAAGCAGCGGCUCCUGGACCGCAUUCACAGCAUCACUGCCGAGAGGCUCAUCUUCAGCCACGCUGUGCAGAUGGUGCAGUCGGCUGCCCUGGACGAGAUGUUCCAGCACCGUGAGGGCUGCGUCCCACGCUACCACAAGGCCCUGCUGCUCCUGGAGGGGCUGCAGCACAUGCUCUCGGACCAGGCCGACAUCGAGAACGUCACCAAGUGCAAGCUGUGCAUUGAGCGGAGACUCUCGGCGCUGCUGACUGGCAUCUGUGCCUGACCUUUCUGGCCUGGCUGGGCCCCCCGUCCUGCCGAGCCCUGCAGAGUGGGCUCUGUGUGCUGGCUGGACUCCUCGGGACAAGCCCAUGGCGCUGAUCGCUGGUGCUGAGCCCUGCCCUGGGCCCCACGGACAGUCAGCCUGCCGGCCUCCCUGCAGCUCACGGGGCAGAACCAGCACAUCUGGAGCCACACAGCUUGGGGGGUGUCUCCCAUCUUUUACAGGUGGGGAUCACAGAAUUUCUGCCCCUCCAGCUGCCUGGCUCAGCAGGCGUGGGUGCCACCACCCUCUAGCCCCAGGGCAGCCCCGGAGGACAGGCAAGGGCCUGAGACCACUGCCGACUCAAAGCCAAAGCGAGCUCCUGCUUAGGGAAGGUCAGCAGGCACUGUGCCCAGGAAGAGCCUGCGGCCUCGGCGUCCCCCAGUCUCCAGGAGCCUCUCCCUCCGAGAUACCCACCCAGCUUUGUCAAUCACCCAAGCACUUUAUGCAUAUAGAGACAGAACCUGGACCUCACCAGGGACUGCUGGGCAGCGAUUCCUGGCAGUGGCCUGGUGUUUGUACAUACACAUAUGCAGACACAUGCCAGGGCCCCCCAAGCCCGAGCACCGGACCACGUUGCUGCCCAGGUCUGGACCUCAGCGGGAGAACUGGCUCCGGGGGGAGUGGGGCCCUGCGCUAGAGGCAGAGGCAGUUCUUUGUUCAAGCGUUCCUCUGGGGACCGGCAGCAGAGGCACCGUGUUCUCUCAGCCCUGGAUACGUCUUGUAAUCUUUCACACUUUAUUCCUAAAACGUGUCUUAUUUUUAUGCAGCUCAUUUUUUCUUUAAAGGAGAAAACUUGUAGGUGUUUAAGAAUUGGUUUUGGGAGGGCGAGGACUGGGCCAGGUUAGAGGCAGAUGGCACAGGGGCGUGUGGCGGGCGGGUGAGGCUGCUUUGCACACCUGUGUUGGUGGCUGUCCCCUGCCGCCCCUCCCUGUGGCAGCAGCAGGACAGGUGUGUGCCCAGCACCCUCCCUACCUGGGCCUGGAAGCAGAUGAGGGGAAUACUUCAUGCAAAGAAAAAAGUAACAUGUGCAAAAGCUCCCCGUCCAGCUUUGACAGUCAGUUUUGAUGUCAGCUCCUCGGCAGGGUAGGCCUGAUGACAGCCCUGUCCCUCCCUGCCUCUGCCUUGCCCAAGGCCACGGAGGGCAUCUGCAGAGAGGCCUGCCUUCCGGAUUCCAGGCGGGCAUGCCCUGCAAACCCCGCCUGGGCCUCCCUUGGUCUGCCCAGCCCUCGAUUAGCCCUGCCUGAAUCAGUAGAUACUUGAACGAGUCCCCAGUCUGCGGGAGGCAGUGGUGGGGCCAUGGACCCAUGCGGGGGGUUCCAGGGUCACACGCCACAUAACAGACAAAAAUACACACACGUGUGUUUUUCUUUGCAAUACUUGAAAUAUUGCCACUGUGCUUGGACUUAGAAGAAGAAAAUCCCCGUGACUUCUUCCUCAUCACCUUGAUGGCUUUAUUCUCACCUUGUGGGGCAUGUUUGUAUUUAUUGCUUCAUGGCCGACUGGAAUCCUGAGUCCUGGGAAGCUGGCACUGCGGGGAUCUUGCCCGGUGUCCUGGUCCUCUUGCUUCCGUCGCGGCCGCAUGUGCGUGUGUCCAAGCAGGUCCUGGGCGCCUCAACUGCUGCCCCUGGUUGAAUGUUCUCUUGAUAGUGCUGGACCCUUUGUCUAUUUUAAAGCGAAUUUUGUGUGAUUUCCUGCCCUUUGCGUUAUAUUGUAUAAUACCAACGUAAGGAAAUAAACCUUUGGAAUUGUU